ACCCGAACUUCAAGCCAGCAGAGGCCAUGUCAUCCUAAGCUAGGGAUAGGGGAGGCUCGCCGGGAUGAGCCUUUGGCUUAACCUAACCUCUGCUCCCUACUUCUGCCUCACCCCAGUCUCAGAUGACGGGAGGCCAAUGCCAAAGACGGAUAGGAUCUAUAGAGGCAGUCCUCUUCUAGGACUGGGACACAACAGUGCAUGAGGCAACUGACAGGGGUGAUGUAAAGCUGUUGUGUCUCCAUCCUGGUUGCCCCAGUUCUAGCAGGUGAUGUGACACUACGGUGGUCGCUGCCCAGAUUGAGAAGUGGAAGGGGGUGUUGCUGGCCGCUAGAAACACUCAUAAUUCCACUGAGUUUGAGGCUCUGGUAGGGGCGCAUGUGGGCAUGGGAAGGAGCCCUGCACUCUGAGCACAGCCUCUCAGAUGUAACGCAGUGGCUCUGGGAGGUCAAAGUCUCAGCCCAGUGGGAGCUCUGACAAAAGGAGGAGAAACCCCCCCAGUAGACAUGUGGCUCUGUCUGAUCCACUCCUGCCGCCCCUUCUGGCAACUUCCCUGGGGAGGGAGGACCUGCUUCCCAGCAGGACCUUCAUCGAGUCACUGUAGGGGCAGGUAGAGUGGGCCAGGGAGCCACAGCUGAAUGGCACUCAAGGGCCAUCACUAGGCAUUGCCUCUCCAUUCCUGAGUGUGGGGCAAGGGUCCCUGCUGAGUUUUACUCUUAGCAGUGGGCUUCCAGAUCCCCAUGCUCCUGGGUUCUUGACUGCCUCCCUCUUCAGAGGUAAGACACAUGGCUGGACCAAGGCCUCCAGGGGACAGCCCUGCCAUCAAGGAAGACAGCACAGGACUGGGACCCACCCAUGAACCCUUCUCAGGACAACCCAACAGCACCAGUGGGGAUGUUCUCCUAAGCCGCAGAGGGCCUGGGCACGCCAUCCGUCCUCCAGGAAGAGCCAUGGUGUUAAUGCAGGACAAGGGCAGCUCUCAGCAGUGGCCUGGUCUGGGGGGCGAGGGUGGUGGCACAGGUCCCUUAAGCAUGCUCAGAGCUGCCCUGCUGCUCAUCAGCCUGCCAUGGGGGGCCCAAGGGACAGCCAGCACCAGCCUCAGCACUGCUGGGGGUCACACCGUGCCACCGACUGGGGGCCGCUACUUGAGCAUUGGAGAUGGCUCUGUGAUGGAGUUUGAGUUUCCUGAGGACAGUGAGGGCAUCAUCGUGAUCUCCAGCCAGUACCCAGGCCAGGCCAACAGGACGGCGCCUGGCCCCAUGCUCAGGGUCACCUCCCUGGACACAGAGGUGCUGACCAUCAAGAACGUGAGUGCUAUAACCUGGGGAGGCGGGGGUGGCUUUGUGGUGAGCAUCCACUCAGGCCUGGCUGGGCUGGCCCCACUCCACAUCCAGCUCGUGGACGCCCAUGAGGCCCCGCCCACACUGAUUGAGGAGCGGAGAGACUUCUGCAUCAAGGUCUCACCUGCUGAAGACACGCCUGCCACCCUCAGCGCCGACCUGGCCCACUUCUCGGAAAACCCAAUCCUCUACCUGCUCCUGCCUCUUAUCUUUGUCAACAAGUGUUCGUUUGGGUGCAAAGUGGAACUCGAGGUUCUGAAGGGGCUCAUGCAGAGCCCCCAGCCCAUGCUGCUGGGCCUCCUGGGCCAGUUUCUGGUCAUGCCCUUGUACGCUUUCCUCAUGGCCAAGGUCUUCAUGCUGCCCAAGGCCCUGGCUCUGGGCCUCAUCAUCACCUGCUCGUCGCCUGGCGGCGGGGGGAGCUACCUCUUCAGCCUCCUUCUUGGAGGGGACGUCACCCUGGCCAUCUCCAUGACUUUCCUCUCUACGGUGGCUGCCACUGGCUUCUUGCCUCUGUCUUCGGCCAUCUACAGCCGCCUGCUCAGCAUCCAUGAGACGCUCCACGUGCCCAUCUCCAAGAUCCUGGGGACCCUGCUGUUCAUUGCCAUCCCCAUAGCCGUGGGCGUGCUGAUCAAGUCCAAGCUCCCCAAGUUCUCCCAGCUGCUGCUGCAGGUCGUCAAGCCCUUCAGCUUUGUGCUCCUCCUGGGCGGCCUCUUCCUGGCCUAUCGCAUGGGGGUCUUCAUCCUGGCAGGCAUCCGGCUACCCAUCGUACUGGUGGGUAUCACGGUGCCCCUGGUUGGCCUGUUGGUGGGCUACUGCCUAGCCACGUGUCUGAAGCUGCCAGUGGCCCAGCGGCGGACGGUCAGCAUUGAGGUAGGGGUGCAGAACAGCCUGCUGGCCUUGGCCAUGCUGCAGCUAUCCCUCCGCCGCCUUCAAGCUGACUAUGCCUCCCAGGCCCCCUUCAUUGUGGCGCUGAGCGGCACCUCCGAGAUGCUGGCCUUGGUCAUUGGCCACUUCAUCUACAGCAGCCUGUUCCCAGUUCCCUGAGGCCUCUGGGUCAAGCUUUCAUCAGCCCCAGCCCCCACACUCCACCAAAGUUCUCAUGCACUAUGCACUCAGAAAAAUCCAGGCUUAUUUUUUUUACUGAUUUUUUAUUCUCCAGCUUUCAGUGCCAAAGAGGCCAUGCUGAGUUAGGUAGGUGGGCGCUGCCCAGAAAAUAUAUUUCAAUAAAAGAGAGAAGCAA